GGUACUACUGGCGGGAGGAGUAAAGAUGGCGGCGCGAGGGUCUCCGCCCUCUGCUCCGGGCUGAAGCGCUCUGAGAGAGGCGGCAGCGGCAACUCGAGCCCCAACAGUAAUUUAGUGUUGGUAGUUUUGGCAGCAGCUGCCGAGGCCGGAGCAAUGGCGGAACUGGAGCACCUAGGAGGGAAGCGGGCAGAGUCGGCGCGAAUGCGGCGGGCAGAGCAGCUUCGGCGCUGGCGGGGCUCGCUGACAGAGCAGGAGCCUGCGGAGCGACGAGGCGCGGGGCGGCAGCCGCUGACCAGGCGCGGGAGCCCCAGGGUCCGCUUCGAGGACGGUGCUGUCUUUCUGGCCGCCUGCUCUAGCGGGGACACCGACGAGGUGAGAAAGCUUCUGGCAAGAGGUGCUGAUAUCAACACGGUCAACGUGGACGGCUUGACAGCCCUGCACCAGGCAUGUAUUGAUGAAAAUUUGGACAUGGUGAAGUUUCUGGUGGAGAACAGAGCCAAUGUAAACCAGCAAGACAACGAGGGCUGGACACCCCUUCAUGCAGCAGCUUCCUGUGGCUAUCUCAACAUAGCAGAGUAUUUCAUUAAUCACGGAGCCAGUGUAGGUAUUGUCAAUAGUGAAGGUGAAGUUCCCUCUGACCUUGCAGAAGAGCCAGCCAUGAAGGAUCUUCUUCUGGAGCAAGUAAAGAAGCAAGGAGUUGAUCUAGAGCAGUCAAGAAAAGAAGAAGAGCAGCAGAUGUUGCAGGAUGCCCGCCAGUGGCUCAACAGUGGGAAAAUAGAGGAUGUGAGGCAGGCUCGCUCAGGGGCUACAGCCCUUCAUGUGGCUGCUGCCAAGGGCUACUCUGAAGUCCUCAGACUUUUAAUUCAGGCUGGCUAUGAACUCAAUGUUCAGGAUUAUGAUGGCUGGACUCCCCUCCAUGCUGCUGCACACUGGGGAGUGAAGGAGGCUUGCUCCAUCCUGGCAGAAGCACUUUGUGACAUGGAUAUUCGAAAUAAACUGGGCCAGACACCAUUUGAUGUGGCUGAUGAGGGUCUCGUGGAGCAUUUGGAGUUGCUCCAGAAGAAGCAGAAUGUGCUUCGAAGUGAAAAGGAGACACGGAAUAAACUCAUUGAGUCAGAUCUGAACAGCAAGAUUCAGAGUGGGUUCUUUAAGAACAAAGAGAAGAUGCUCUAUGAGGAGGAGACACCUAAGUCCCAAGAAAUGGAGGAAGAAAAUAAAGAAUCUAGUAGCUCCAGCUCAGAGGAGGAGGAAGGUGAAGAUGAAGCUUCUGAGUCAGAAACUGAGAAGGAGGCAGAUAAAAAGCCAGAAGCCUUUGUCAAUCAUUCCAACUCUGAAAGCAAGAGUAGUAUCACAGAGCAGAUACCAGCACCAGCUCAAAAUACCUUCUCUGCCUCUUCUGCUAGGAGGUUCUCUUCUGGCCUUUUUAACAAGCCAGAAGAGCCCAAAGAUGAAUCUCCUUCUUCAUGGAGAUUGGGACUGAGAAAAACUGGCAGCCACAACAUGCUGAGUGAGGUGGCCAAUUCCAGGGAACCUAUAAGGGACCGAGGCUCUUCCAUCUAUCGCUCCUCUUCAAGCCCUCGGAUUUCUGCUCUACUGGACAACAAAGAUAAGGAGAGAGAAAACAAAAGCUAUAUUAGUUCACUAGCACCCCGGAAGCUCAACAGCACAAGUGAUAUUGAAGAAAAGGAGAACAGAGAAUCAGCUGUUAAUCUAGUGAGGAGUGGCUCCUAUACCCGGCAGCUAUGGAGGGAUGAAGCAAAAGGAAAUGAAAUCCCACAGACAAUUGCUCCCUCCACCUAUGUAUCAACUUACUUGAAAAGUGCUUCAUUUGGUAGAAGUAGUGACCCCACAAGUCCCUACAUUUCAGCCAAUCGCAAUUCAUCUCCUGCUACCUCACCCAUUACCAUUGGUUCAUCUACCUCUCGGGGCAGCCAGUGGCAACCUGCCUCUUCUUGCCCUGCACCAAUCAGUGCAAACACUACUGCAUCUGUACAUCAUGGCAGGACUCCUCACAAAUCCCAGGCCGACACAACAGCAGAGAAAACAGCAGACAAUGUCUCUUCUAGCACCCCGCUCUGUGUGAUCACCAAUCGCCCUCUUCCUAGCACUGCCAAUGGGGUUACAGCUACUCCUGUGCUCUCCAUUACUGGAACAGAUUCCUCUGUGGAAGCCAGGGAGAAGAGGAGGUCCUAUCUGACUCCUGUACGGGAUGAGGAAGCAGAGUCUUUACGGAAAGCACGCUCCAGACAAGCUCGGCAGACACGAAGGUCUACUCAAGGUGUCACCCUAACAGACCUUCAAGAAGCAGAAAGGACAUUCAGCCGGUCGAGGGCAGAGAGGCAAGCUCAGGAGCAGCCUCGUGAGAAGCCCACAGACACUGAAGGGCUUGAGGGGAGCCCUGAGAAGCAUGAGCCCUCAGCAGUUCCAGCAACAGAAGCUGGGGAGGGCCAGCAGCCCUGGGGCAGGAGUCUGGAUGAAGAGCCUAUCUGUCAUCGCCUGAGGUGCCCAGCUCAGCCAGACAAACCCACCACGCCAGCAUCUCCUUCUACGUCAAGACCCUCACUCUACACCAGUUCCCACCUGCUAUGGACAAAUAGAUUUUCAGUCCCUGAUUCUGAGAGUUCAGAGACUACCACAAACACUACAACUGCAAAGGAAAUGGACAAAAAUGAGAAUGAAGAAGCAGAUUUGGAUGAGCAGUCCUCUAAGAGGCUGUCCAUCCGAGAGAGGAGGCGGCCCAAGGAACGACGAAGAGGCACAGGCAUCAAUUUCUGGACAAAGGAUGAGGAUGAAACUGAUGGCUCUGAAGAGGUCAAAGAAACGUGGCAUGAAAGACUUUCUAGGUUGGAAUCGGGAGGUAGUAAUCCUACAACCAGUGAUUCUUACGGUGACCGGGCUUCAGCAAGAGCCCGUCGGGAGGCCCGGGAGGCCCGCCUAGCCACCCUGACCAGCCGUGUAGAAGAAGACAGCAACAGAGAUUAUAAAAAACUCUAUGAGAGUGCUCUGACUGAAAACCAAAAACUGAAAACAAAACUUCAGGAAGCCCAGCUAGAGCUAGCAGAUAUAAAGUCCAAGCUUGAGAAGGUGGCCCAGCAGAAACAAGAAAAGACCUCUGACCGAUCAUCAGUGCUGGAGAUGGAGAAACGGGAGAGGCGAGCCUUGGAGCGCAAAAUGUCAGAAAUGGAGGAAGAAAUGAAGGUGUUAACAGAACUGAAAUCCGACAACCAGAGGCUGAAAGAUGAAAAUGGUGCCCUCAUCAGAGUCAUCAGCAAACUGUCCAAGUAGGCUAGGCUCCAGAUUUAUGAGGAAAGAAAGGGACAGCAUUUGCUGCCCCCACCCCUCUUUUCCAGUCCUUGCCUUCCAACCAAAAGAAAUGGAUGUUUUGGUGGAAGGACACUUCUUUCUAUCACCCUCUUCAGUCACCUCUAUACACUCUACAUUUUCUCUGCACUUUCAAUGCCCUGUUCUUCCAAACCCCUAUCCCAAGUUUUAUGACAGUUUUAAUUGAAGCAUGAUUGUGGUAAUUCGAGCCAUCUGGAGAAUGCUCUGGGGAGUACACCAGGCUCAGCUGUGGACCCCUCAACUUCCUGCUGCUCAGCUACUUUGUCCACAUUGGAUUUGGUCCAAACAUGUAAGACUUCUACCCUAAUCAGUAUCCUUCAGCUUUUUACAUUAACCCAGUGUCCUCUGAUAUAGGUGAGUCUUGUGGUAGCCACUCCAGGAUCCUGAUUGGGGUGCCAAGAGAAACAGCAGGAUGUUGAAUUGAUCAUCAGAUGCCCUCUGGAAUGGUUAGCAUCCAAGGUGACAGUGACUGCAUUGAGGCGCUCUAUUCUUCUUCACCUCUCAGGAACUGACUUUUAUUUUUUCUGUCAACACCCAGUAAUCUCCCUAACUAGUUUUAACCCUUAUUCCUCCCUCAUACCUAGCCAUUUCUCCAAGGCGCAAAUGGCCCUGGCUUCAUUUAUUCCUUUCCUUUCUAUCCUUUUAUAUUUUUCCCUUCCCCACCCCCUCACUCAAUGGUAUAAAAGCUAGGACAGAGCACCUGACCUCAGUUGUCUUUGGCCAUUGUGGGAAGUCAUUAUUCUGGAGACAAGAAAAUCAUCACUCUGGUGCCUUGGUGGCAGCACCACUGCCUGCUCCCUGGAAGGUAGACUAUGGCAUAAGUGUCAGCUCAUUGUUUUCGUCUCCCACUUAUCUUCCCCCUUCAAAGUGAUUUUCUUUAUAAGAAAAUUUGGGCUCUGAAUACUCCAUUCUGCCUCACUUCCUUGACCUUGUUUUCCUCUCUUCGCCCUGACACCUGCUUCUAAUGAGAAAUGAAGUCAGUGCAAGGAGGAAUGAGAGGUGGGGAGGGGAGAUUGUUGAGAGAUGGACUAGGAAGUGGAAGCAGGCUGGAAAGACACAUAUGGCGAAAGUCAAGUAUCUGAGGCCACUUGCAACAUUGUGACAAAGAAGAUGGAAGAUAGCAGCCUACUGGGCUGUGAGAAUAGUGGUGAAUUUGAUUAUUUCCAGUGGUUAGAUUUAGCAGAGAGAUUUACUUUCUUAGAAAUUAAUAGGGGAAAUGGCACUUAAUAGAGGUUUAAUGGAAUGAAGUACUUUCAACCCAUUGAUGAGAGUCAUGGAAGUUUAGAGUGGCAAGACCCAGAGGUCAUUAGGUCCAGCUUUCUAUUAUUGUGUCACAGGGACCCCUGCUACCACAGCUUUCACCCAUGGGCAUGGUCAGGUAGCCUCUGGUGGCUAUGCAUUUAUUACUCAAAAGUUGGGCAACUCUAAUAACGAGAGAGUUUUUCCUCAUAUCAGCUGAAGUCUGCCUGUGGAUUCUCCUUGUAGUCCAGAUCUACUAUCUGCAACUCUUUAACGGCACUUGAGAUAUGUGCAGUGGGUGGUCUCCCCCUCAGUCUUACUUUGAGCUGCUGUUACUCUAGUCCUUUAAGUCAUUCCUCAUAUGGCAUGCUUUUCUUACCUGUCACAUCUUGGCCAUCCUCCUCUAGACAAAACCAGCCUUUAAAAUAUCAUGUCCAGGCCUGGAAAGAAUACAAAUCCAGUGCAAAAUUAAACCAUUAGUUCUUGAUGAUAACCUAGCAUUAAUACUUACAGUAUUUUCUUUUUGUAGGAGUUUUAUCCCUUGGUUCACUUGAGUGUGCAAGUCAUUAAAUCCUCAUCAUUUUAGGGUUGCCAGUGAUAUUCAGUGUUUAGAGUGGUUCAUUCCCUUAAUAUAUACUACCUCUGUCUGUUAAUUCUUUCCUAACAUGACAUGUAGCUCUCCAUGGUCCUCCCUCUGAAACACCACAUGCUGUUUAAACUAGAAGCUGUAAUUCAAGAUCCCAAUUCCACCAGGUGCAGUGGCUCAUGCCUGUAAUCCCAGCACUUCAGGAGGCCGAGGUGGACAGAUCACGAGGUCAGGAGUUCGAGACCAUCCUGGCUAACACGGUGAAACCCAAUCUCUACUAAAAAUACAAAAAAUUAGCCAGGCGUGGUGGCAGGCGCCUGUAGUCCCAGCUACUCAGGAGGCUGAGGCAGGAGAAUGGCGUGAACCCGGGAGGCGGAGCUUGCAGUGAGCCUUGAUCACGCCACUGCACUCCAGCCUGGGUGACAGAGCAAGACUCCAUCUCAAAAAAAAUAAUAAUAAUAAAUAAAUAAAAAAUCCCAAUUACAGAACAGGAGAUAUGUUUCCUCUGACAAAACCCCAUUUUUAGAGUGUAUAAAAUUCUGUCUUUCAUUUCCAACCAUUUUUCAAGAGAAGCUGCUACUAUCUUGAGACUUCGUAUUAUCAUGGGAGUACUGUAAGUUCAGUUCUCAGGGAAUGCUAAAUUAGAGUAAUAAGUUUUAUAUCCUUCAUUCUGGGAGAGGAAAUCAACAUAAGGUGUUGACUAAUUGAUUAUCCUGGAACAUUUUGAAUAUUGGGGAAGGAAGAUGAUACUUCUUUCUCAAGAAAAGAAAAUUGGAUUAUUAGGAAUACAUCUUGACCCUUUUCCACUCAAUAGACCAGGGAAAGGGGUUACAGAGAGCCUCCUCAGAUCUGUUUGUGCCUUUCAAAAGUACUGGGGGCAGAUUCUCAAAACUCUUAGAUUGGUGUUGCAUCCCUGCCACUUCACAUGACCCUUCCAUGUUAAAGCUGACUUUUCUUGCCAGAAAGUUUUCCUUGUGACAAGAAAUUUGCAAGCUUUUCAAUCUCAGGAAUACUGGAUUCUAUAGCCAAGAACUCAUGAAAGUAAGUGUAAACUAUCCUAGGUAAUUUCAGGUACUUUCUCUUAUGCAAUUAAUUUUAUUAACUGAUUUCUGGUCUAUCUCCAGAGAUAAAAUACCAUUCCUUCACAACUGUAUUGUCUGGAAGCCCCAUGAGAUGGUAAUUAUAGGCCUUCUACUAGCCAGCAGUUCUCUCUGGAUACUGGCAUCAGCAGGUCUCCUUUUUCUUGUGCUGCUUGGACAGGUACCUACUGCUGGCCUCUUCAGUGGCCACAAUCCUCAGUCCUCACCUGCUGGUUUGGAGACUCAUGAGCACCCCAGGCAGCUCAAGCUGAAUAAAUAGCUGCAGACAUGGCCAACAACAUGGGGCUCAGGUCUGUCACUUAACUUAGAGUCUUUACAUGAAAUAUCAGAAUGGGAAAGAGAAUGUUCCUGGUAAAACUCUGUUUUCAUUAAUUUGUUAUUUUUCAAAAACCGAGCCACACCUUUGGAAGUAAUGAUUUGGCCAUUCCAGAGAUUCUGGGGCUAAAGUUUGUUUUUCCAGGGCUGCUGAUCCUUUUCCAGAUAGCUCCAGAGUAUGAUGACCCCAGCCCCAUCCCAAUCUCUAGCGAAAGGGUUAUGCAAAUCUCAGGGUGUUGCCUCUAAAGAAUCUAAAGAAUAGACAUGCUUUGGGCUUACUCAGUGUACCAGAUUCUCUAGUGGGCCAUUCUCAUUUGAUGUUCCCUAGAACCUCCCUGUCUUCCAACUGCAGGAUGUGUUUACUUCUCUUCUGGGCUUCCCCUGGUUUCUGUCCUAGUUCCCACCCCAAGUUUAAGAAGACUUAGAUUCAUUUAUUGCUAUCUGAGGCCACUAGUGAGAUUUCAGAUCUCUCUUUUGCAACAUUUUACCCAUUUCCCUUCCCCAAACCAUGUGCUUAUUAGAUGGUUCCACUCAGGAAGCAAGGAAGCUAAAACUCAAGUUAAUGGUCUGUGGAUCCCACGAAAGUGUGUGUAAACUACUGACUGUUUCUCCACUAGAGGCAUUUAAUUGAGCCAAAGAUGAUGGAAGAAGAAACUCUCAAAGCCAUGUACUUUGUUAGGUGUCUGGAUUUUUGGCCUGUUUGCAGCCUCUCCUAGCCACAGACAGACACUGUCUCCUCUCAGAGAAAGGCCAGUGUUUCGGUCCAGGCCACUGGUGAGUGUCGGCACCCUUGAGGUGGGCAUGGAGUGAGCAGAAGAAGCCUGGAGAAGAGAGAACUAUUUAAAAGUGUUGCCAGUUAUUCAGCUUCCAGGCGGCUUUGCACCUCCAAAGGUGCAAAAAGGAAAAAGAAAGCAGAAAGGAUUCAGCAUUUAAGCAGAAAGAAAAGGGAAAUUCUACUCUACCAGAUGAGCCACUGGUUCCACUGGAGCUUAUCAGUGAAGUAACACUGCAGGAGCCCUGGUAUCCUUCCCUCAGAGAUAUCAUCAGGGGCCCUCAAACCCCAUUGUUUAUGCCAGCACUGACCGCACUUUAAGCACACACUUACCAAUCAGAGGUCGUGUAAUUGGCCUAAAUCUAGGCCCAGUUAUUACUACAAAUCUUAGUCACCAUACUCUCUCGCCCAGGCUGGAGUGCAGUGGUGUGAUCUCAGCUCACUGCAACCUCCACCUCCCAGGCUCAAGGGAUCCUCUCACCUCAGCUCCCGAGCAGCUAGGACUGCAGGUGUGCACCACCAUGCCCAGCUAAUUUUUGAAUUUUUUUGUAGAGAUGGGGUUUUGCCAUGUUGCCCAGGCUGGUCUGAAGCUGCUGGGCUCAAGCAAUCCACCUGGCUGGGCCUCCCAAAGCGAUAGGAUUACAGGCGUAAGGGCCCACGCCCAGCCUACCAUACUGAUUUUCAAGGCAGGGUCUAACCCUUCAUAAGAUGUGAGUUCUUCCAACCCAAUAAGCAGGCAGCUUUGAGGACAAAAAGGCAACAUUAAAAGAUAAGACCCUAGAAGUCAGAACAUCUGUAUUCCAAGGCCACCCCUUCUCCUUUUAGUCAUGUGACUUUGGGCAGGUCACCCUCCCUGUCUGUAAAAUGAGGUUGGACUGGAUAAUCUUUAUGUGCCCUUUCCUUUUGGCUUAAAAUUCUGUGAUUUAUUCAUUCUUAGGAAGAUCAGCAUAUUUAUUGGGAUUUCUGCUUCAAAAAUUCUUUCUAACCUCAAAAAUCCAAGUCCAGAAUUUUUUGUUUUCUUCUGGAUUUAAACUGUUUAAUAUGAGCACAUCAAGGUUGACUUCUCAUCCUUUUUGGGAAGUGAAUUUAAUAUUGAGGGUAAUUGAAUGAUGUUGCAAUGGCUUUCCCUCCUGCUGGCUUGGUAAGAAUAUUAAAGCCUGCAGAGGUGGAAAUUGGAGCUCAUGGAGAAAUGGAUAGAAAGCAAUUUGUUGCAGGCAGCCUUUGGACAAGUUGUUUUAAUAGGAAAUAGACCUGCUGCUUCAUAGGUUUCCUCAACCACCUUUCCUCAGCUUUCUUAAAAUGGGAUCUACAUUGGCUCUUCACACCCAAAUAGCAGACUAAUCGUUUUUCUGCUUAGCACCGUCUGGUUCAUUGUCUUGAACUCUGCCUUACAGCAGCAAGAAAAUUUUCCUCGACAAGAACCUCAAUCUUUAGUUCCAUUGAGCUCCCCCUCUGGAUUUUGGACUUACCAGAAGUAGGAGGUUCUGAUACCAUUCAAGAUGGUCUUUCCUUCAAAGCAGGUCUGAAGAGGAGACUACCAAAGCAGUGUUUACAAACCCAGAGUCCACACAACCAUAUUGCAUAGAACAGCACUUGGCUUUCACAAGCCUCCUACAGGACCUGGUGUAAUUGGAGUGAAAGGGCAGAGACCCUGGAAGUGGAGGUGGCUGUGUGCUGCGAUGGGAAGAAGGCAGAAGGCCCAGGGGCUUUGGACAUAGAGCAGGGUGGAAGCUGCAAGUACUGGGAAGGAAGAGAGUUUCACAGAAACAAAGCUUUGUCACACAGAAAUGAGUUCUGUCUCACUGGUGACUUCAUCCCUCAGGCUCCAGCUGAGCAGAGAUUUUAAUCAGCUUCCUUAAUGGGUAUUGACACUGCUCAGGAAGCAGUAGACCCUGUCAGGGACAGCUAUUGAUCUUUUGUGUUCUGAUUAGAUUGGAAAAUAGAUCAACUUCAUUGUAGUCCAGGAACUGUUGGUCACAGCUACUAGGAAUGAGGUGAUUUCUGAGGGCUGAGAAAAAACACAGAAUCUUGGCCAGCAGCCAGCAGCUGCAUGGUGAAAGAUGCAUUCACUUCUCCUUUGAGAGUUGGGGUUGAGGGCAAACAUAGAACCCAGGUUUGGCUUACAACCCAGUGUCCCGGAAGCCCUCCUUCGGGAGAACUGUAAGUAAGAGGUGGGUGUGUCUAAAGACAAUACCAUUAAUGAAUGUUCUGGCCUUACCUAAAAAGGUUUAGCAAUUUGGGGAUAACUCUUGGAUCUAGCUUAUGUGCGUUCACAUGCACAUUUGCUAGCCCAGAGCUUUUAAAAUGAGGUCUGGCAUAUACUUGAUUACAAAUGAAAACUCAGAAACCAAUUUUAUUUAUUAAAUCAUAUCUUUUGUUUUUCCCCCUCCCUUCUAAUCCCCCAAAGGACCUAUUUGAGCUGUUCCCCAAUUCAUCUGCUUAUUUUGGACCAUGAAUCUGCCAGAGUGAUAUUUUCUGUUAUUUCUCCUCCAAAUUUUUCCCUGAUGUUUCCAAUAAAGAUUUACUUGGGUGGCCCCUUAAGGUGACAUCAGGAUGCUCUUAUGUCCUUCCAGAAUAAGCAUACACUUCACUCCUCUCCCUUUCAUCUCCCUCUGCAUUCUUAAUUCCUUGCUUUUCUCACUUGGAGCCGAGGGUGCUUUAGAGAGGUGGUUUUCCAUGAAUCAGCCAAGAUUCCUGUAGAAGUUGGGUAUACCAACCACCACCACCACCGCCCCCUAUUCCAGUUUCAAAGCUCCUCGGCUAUGCUAAUGUCCCCUCAGAGAUGAGGUUUGACUUUUAGGCCCGUAUGACUCCUCCAUAGCCUGGCCAAGGAGACCAUGAGUAGCCAUGUCUGGUUUACUCUUUAUCCUGAGACUGUUUAUAGCUUAAAACAGAAGUGUGUCUUCCCAGCACAAACCUAAUCAAUCAGUGUAUCAGUGCAUCUGGUGGCAACAGCUCAGCCCAUUCAAAGAGCAAGGAUUCAGGAAAGGCACACUGAUGGUGGGGAGCCUCUUAAGAGCCUCUAAUGUUCUCCCAAAACCAGAGUUGAGAGUCGGAGUGCCAGUCGUCGGGGCCCACUAUUCCUGAAUAAGGGACAUGCAAGGGCCAGAAGUAGCUUGACUCUCGCCUAAAUAUCUGUGCCUUUGCCUGUCCUUUCUCCCACUCUACUGAAACCCGGAACAGAUUCCCGCUUGCCUUCUGAUGAAGAGAGGUUAGGUAAAGAGAGUUUGGAGGAAAAAAGACACCAGGAGGCAGGCUGCGGGGUAGGAGAGGGUUCUGAGAGGAGGCAGCAAUCCAGAAUACCUCCUUUUCUAGCCAGCAUCCCUUGAACUUUUGAAAGGUUGUGCCUACCACUGGCUGGCACACCAGGGCAAUGAUUUCCCUGCAGAAGGAAGGAAAGAAUGUUUCACCCUUGCAUCCUUCUUGGAGAAGCUACAGCCUGUGCUCAGUUGAGUGGUUCACACUCAGACUUUGGCUUUAUGGUUUUCCUUCCUCCUUGUCUUUGCCCUGACCUUGAUCAACAGGGGUGAAAAGAACCACCCUGAGGUUUCCAUGCCUCUCCCAUUUUAGUGGUAGCAUUUUGUGUCUUUACUCCACCCUUCACCCUAGUUCCACCAAGGUUCACACACCAGAUGUAACUGUUUUUCAGCUGAGUUGUAUGGAUUAACUUCAGUCCACUGUAAAUACACCUGGGAUGGGGUGGGGUUGGGGUUGUUUAGGGAGAAGCAGCCAGACUUGCUUUGUGAACUGAAUGUAUUUUUAUGCAAUUUUGAGUGGCCUUUCAACCCUAAGAUGAAUGGUUUUGUUUUACUGGUUGUUGUUAUAUAGUUUUGAGUAUUCUGUGUUUGAAAGUUUGGGAAUAAUAAUAUUCACUUCUAUAUGAUGCCUGUAAACACAACAGUAUUUAUAAAUGAGUAAAUAAAACUGUGUUUUAACUUUGUGACUGUCUCCACAGUUCAGAGCAUGGGAUUUCUAGAAUCUCACAUCUGGGGCAGCCUCUUCUGAUUUUACAUCUUAUCAUUGGUGGGGGCCUCGCCCACCAGCCUCCUACAACUCCUGUCCACAUAGAGGCCCCUUCCCCAGGGACAGCCACAGUGAGUCAUGGCCACUGAGAAGGGUCUCUGGUAGUAUCAAGGAAUUUCCUAAAUGGAGUCAGGCCAAGGAGAAGCCUAGAUUGGCGUUCAAAAGAACCGUAAGAUAGAUAGAUAGAUAGAUAGAUAGAUAGAUAGAUAGAUAGAUAGAUAUCAAGGUUCCAAGCUUCAAGUAACCAAGAGUAUAUACGGUUAUUUCUUGGAAGACACCAGGUUUAAGUGACAAAGGUGUUGAGGCCAUCCAGGUGAACACUAGCACACUCUAGUACAUGGGAAAGUUGAGGUCUAGGGAGGUGGUGAUUUCCUUGGGCUCAUGGAAGUCUCCUGCCAUCACCCUUAGUCAUCUGCUAUAUCCAUAAGUCUUCAUGAGGUCAUUGUUUAAUUCAGGAGAUCCAAAACUAUCCUGUAGUUCCAAACUACAAAUGUAGUUAACUUGGGGGCUAUUGAAGGUUAAAUCUAAACUCAAAAUGAAGGAGCCAUGCCCAGAGAAGAGCUGUUCAGGCCCGCUGGCAGGGUUUGUACGUGGGUGGCCAGGUCUGACCCCAGGCAGCCAGGAUCUGGGUCUGGUUUCUCCAUCCAGCAAGCCCUGCCUCUGGCUUUGCUCAGCCCUGUGUUUCCUGCCAAGCGGAAAUCCCUGGUCACUGACUUGGGGAGAGGUCAGGGAGGGAAGAUUCUUCUCCCCUGAUGUCACCCAGCUGUUUGUAACCCAAGCAGCAGCAGAACAAGCACACUUGAUGUCAUGGUUGAAGAAUUCAGUCCUGUCCUGGGGCACAAAACAGAGGCAAAGAAGCAUGACCGAUGCAAAGGGUUCCUAGACUGCAAAUGUCAUUUCUCUUUCUGACCCCCACUGGUUGUAGUAAGGUCUGCAGAUACAGUAUCACCUAGCCGUCACGUGGUCCAGCCCUCUUGGGGGGAAAGGAGAAGGCCACAACCUAUUGGCAGAGUAAAAAGCUCAUAUUCUUAGCCAGGAGACCCUCAGGUGAUAAAUCCCAGUCCGUCUGCUGAAAGGCUCAUGCCCCUCACCCUACCCAGCCUUAGGGACUGAAGCAGCAAGACAGGAUAGAUGUUAAAGGAUCUGGGCUCAUGCUCCCUCAGGUGGGCAGCUCCCAUCCCUGCUUGCAUUCACUGCCCCCAUGCCUUUGGACCUGAUGGACAAGCACACAUCUAGCCAACGGUGUUCCUGGAGGACAGGUGCUGGUGUAAACUGACAAAAAUGGUAGCUGCUGGUCUAUCCUCAAGGAGAGGAGACAGGUGGAAGUGGGAACCGAAGAAGGAGUUUUACUCUUCCCUGGUCUUUGGGGGCAAUGCUGUCCCACUCUCCCUUUCCCUAAAAAUUCUGACGCCCUAUCCCUGGUCCCUAACAUCUUUGCUUCAGAAGUUAAAGACAUUUCAAGUUAUUUGCAAAGAGUCAACUGAGGACUUUGUAGAAAUUGUUACUUUUCAAAUUCCCACUUCCCAGGGCCAGCCUCCCUCUCGUCAUUGGGCUCAGACUGUGGCUGUUCCCUAAGCCCAGCUCUACUGGAAGGGAAUUCAAGAAUAUAGUCCCCACCACCACCCCGCCCCGCCCAGCCUCCCAGACAAUGUUCCCCGGCACCACCACACUCCCCACAGUUCCACAGCCUGGCAUGUGUUCUCAGGAGAUGUGUGGGCCCCAGCACCCACCAGAGUGCCAAUCUGGUCUUCCCCCAACCCCAGGAGAGAGGGGACCUCAGCCCCUUUUGGUGCUUCCCUGAAGGGAGAUUCUGGGUUAGAAGCCAGAGCCUCAGGACCAUCUCACCACCCUCACCCACCAUACUGACCCUCACAGGCAGCUCCCACUCCCUCACCCCCACCUCAGCGCAGCAAAAACAACCAGAGACACCCCCCACCCCCAGGUUUCUUUCAGCUCAUUUCUUUAAUAAGGAGACGCAGUUCAUUACAAAAUAACAAUUUGACAAGAGAUCAGACAAGAACAAGAGUCCACAUAAGGGAGAUGGAGAGCAUUGCCAAGCAGAAGUGGGAAUGAGAGGGCCGGGGGCAAGGGCUGUACAUGUGUCCUUCCUAUGGAGACGAAGGCAGGGCUCCUGGUGGGCUGACCUUGGCGAAGCUAGGCUCUGCCAGGCCCUGAUUUUGAAGUUUUCAGCCCCAGGGUUUUCAGAAAGCAGCAAAUCAAGUCCUUAGAUGGGCAGGAGUCAGGGCAGAAGGGUCACUAUCUUUGAAGAGGCCCCCCUAAAGUCCUGAUCGCUAAGGCAGGUGGGAUGGAGGAACUCCUGGUGCCCCAUGCACACUGCUCCCAUCACCUCACCAGACAGAUGCUCUCUCAACUCUUGCCUCAAUUUGUCUCUGCUGUGGGUGUGGAGAGUGGGAGGGCCCCAGAGAGAGCUGGAGGAAGCAAGACAUGUCUUCACUGGUCCAAGCACCUGAUUCCAGCCUGCUCUGAAAUGGUCCCCUCCACCUUCCCCACUCUUUCAGUUCCCAGCACAAAGGUCCCUGGGACUUCUGUGUGCAACUUCUGUUGUGGUUUGUGCAGGGCAAGCCUGCCUCGCCACCUCUGGCCUCCUCGAAUGCGCCCUGCCUGAUUCCCUUCCCGUUCUCUCUCCUUCCUCAUACUUGUCACAGUUGCCAGGCCUGAGGCAUCCUGGGCUCUUCCCAUGCAGUACUGCCCUCAGGUGCCCAUGGGGCCAGGGGCCGCAGGCAGGGGGGCUACCUGUCCCUCUCAGUUCAACAGGAUGACCUGGGGCCUUGGAAGCCCCCAGGCCCCUCUACUCACCUCUGCUACUUGGUGCAACUGGCUGGGGCUUCUCUGGGGAGCAGGUGUGAAGGUCAGGGGACUUAGUCCACACCUGCUCUGCCUGAGCCUCUCUCACAGCUGAACCUGCCCACCCCACUCUCAGGGGAUCGCUGGUAGCCCUGAGGUUGCCCCGCUAUUGGGCUGCUUUCUGUCAGACUGCAGGAGGAUGCACGAGGGAAGAGCGUCAGCCCCUGUAUUCACCGGCCUCUCCCUGAGUCCCUCCUCCAUCACCACCCACAGACCCUCACACUACAGAGGUGAGUAAGCAGGGAUGGUUCUGUCAUCCCUGGCUGAGCUGCUGACUGGCUGCUCCUGAAAAUCCUGGUUGCCUCCACAGGGACCCCAGGAAAGGUAUCCAGAACCAUGGAGUCCCACUGCUGUCUGCUCCUCGCCCAGCGUAGAGAUGGAGCUGAACUGUGAACCCAGGCCGAGAAAGCCAGCUCGGGCAGGGCCAGCAUGGGCAUCUCCUGAGACCCCACCGGAAGCCCUGGACACCGUCCAUUCUCAUGACACGGGACUGAGGGAGCAGGAGGGAGUGACAACAGGUGAGCCCUUCAGAAGUGGUCUGUGGGGAGCCAGUUGGAGAGACAUGGGGGCUCCUGGGAGGAGCCAAGGGAGGCCAAAUCUCCAGCAGGAGGCCCCCUUUAUGGCUUUUCAGUGAAUUCAAACAGUGGGAGGAAGGGGCACACCACACACAUACACAGAACAUGGAAGCUACUGGGAUGCCAGAUACCAGGCUGGACACUGCACCGGGCCCUGAGGUUUGGCUCUGCAGGCAGAUGUGCAGCAAACAGGCCUUCAGGGCGACAGGGUCCUCCAGCAUCUCCCAAGGCAGGGCUGGACUGGAGCAGGCACCGACUCCCGCCCACUGAUGACUCCCAUGGGGGGUUUCCCGAUGGGAGGAGGCAGGGGUGGGGCUGGGGAACAAAGACUUUACACGACAUAAAAUCAAAGGAGCAGCCUCAACCAGUUCUGUAAAAUGGGUUUGAGGUUGGGGAUCAAGGGGACUCUCAGCAUUGCCAUGCGGCUAUUUACAGAAAGUUAUAGACAUGCAUCUUGAUUAAACAAGAUUCUGUUCAUAUGUUUCUAGGUAAUUAUCUUCUUUUAUAUAUAAUUAAAUAUACACGGAUGGGGGCAGAUGAGGCUCAAAUGGCUUCAGAAGGUUCUUAUUUUGUUGUUGCUUAAAAAAUAAAGUAAUUCAUGUGUCUUCAA